AGAUGCGUCCCGGGGAGUGGGCGGUGACGCGGUGGCAGGUUCUGGGGACAGGCGGUGACCCCAGAAUUGACCCUGGGGACAGGGCGAGGCGCGGAGGCGUCCUGAAGGCGAGGCGGUGACGCAAGAGCGAAUCCUUGGGGCGGGGCGAGGCGUUGGAGAUGCGUCCUGCGGGCGGGACGGUAACGCGGGGGCGGGGCGGUGACGUGAGCGGGCAGGCUCUGGAUCUCGGCGGGAUCAGGCCAGGCAGCUGAUCAUAGAUCUGGAGACUCGAGGGAGUCAGGCUCUUCCUUUGUUCAUCUCCUGCUUAGAGGACACAGGCCAGGACAUGCUGGCUUCGUUUCUGCGAACUAACAGGCAAGCAGCAAAGUUGUCGAAGCCAACCCUAGAAAACCUUACCCCAGUGGUGCUCAGACCAGAGAUUCGCAAACCAGAGGUUCUCAGACCGGAAACACCCAGACCAGUGGACAUUGGUUCUGGAGGAUUUGGUGAUGUCGGUGCUCUUGAGAGUUUGAGGGGAAAUGCAGAUUUGGCUUACAUCCUGAGCAUGGAGCCCUGUGGCCACUGCCUCAUUAUCAACAAUGUGAACUUCUGCCGUGAGUCCGGGCUCCGCACCCGCACUGGCUCCAACAUCGACUGUGAGAAGUUGCGGCGUCGCUUCUCCUCGCUGCAUUUCAUGGUGGAGGUGAAGGGCGACCUGACUGCCAAGAAAAUGGUGCUGGCUUUGCUGGAGCUGGCGCAGCAGGACCACGGUGCUCUGGACUGCUGCGUGGUGGUCAUUCUCUCUCACGGCUGUCAGGCCAGCCACCUGCAGUUCCCAGGGGCUGUCUACGGCACAGAUGGAUGCCCUGUGUCGGUCGAGAAGAUUGUGAACAUCUUCAAUGGGACCAGCUGCCCCAGCCUGGGAGGGAAGCCCAAGCUCUUUUUCAUCCAGGCCUGUGGUGGGGAGCAGAAAGACCAUGGGUUUGAGGUGGCCUCCACUUCCCCUGAAGACGAGUCCCCUGGCAGUAACCCCGAGCCAGAUGCCACCCCGUUCCAGGAAGGUUUGAGGACCUUCGACCAGCUGGACGCCAUAUCUAGUUUGCCCACACCCAGUGACAUCUUUGUGUCCUACUCUACUUUCCCAGGUUUUGUUUCCUGGAGGGACCCCAAGAGUGGCUCCUGGUACGUUGAGACCCUGGACGACAUCUUUGAGCAGUGGGCUCACUCUGAAGACCUGCAGUCCCUCCUGCUUAGGGUCGCUAAUGCUGUUUCGGUGAAAGGGAUUUAUAAACAGAUGCCUGGUUGCUUUAAUUUCCUCCGGAAAAAACUUUUCUUUAAAACAUCAUAAGGCCAGGGCCCCUCACCCUGCCUUAUCUUGCACCCCAAAGCUUUCCUGCCCCAGGCCUGAAAGAGGCUGAGGCCUGGACUUUCCUGCAACUCAAGGACUUUGCAGCCGGCACAGGGUCUGCUCUUUCUCUGCCAGUGACAGACAGGCUCUUAGCAGCUUCCAGAUUGACGACAAGUGCUGAACAGUGGAGGAAGAGGGACAGAUGAAUGCCGUGGAUUGCACGUGGCCUCUUGAGCAGUGGCUGGUCCAGGGCUAGUGACUUGUGUCCCAUGAUCCCUGUGUUGUCUCUAGAGCAGGGAUUAACCUCUGCACUACUGACAUGUGGGGCCAGGUCACCCUUUGCUGUGAGGCUGUCCUGUACAUUGUGGGAUGUUCAGCACUGUCCCUUGCCUCAAUGCCAGUAACGCGUCUUCCUGAGUGGUGCCAAACAAAAAGGUUCUCAGGUGUUGCCAAAUAUGUCCUGGGGUAUAAAACUUUCCUCGCCUGACAACCACUGGUCUGUAGGGAUUUUUGGCUACACACAAACCAGUAUCGCUCAUAGAUCAGCAAACCGGGGCCUACUAGAGUCUGAACAGCUGUAAUCUAUGAAUUCUAAGUGAAAUUUUAAAAAUUGUUAAUUUUUCCUAUAUUGCAUUAAUUUUAAAAAAUAAAUCUGAGGCAAAUAUGGACUCUCUUUUGCCUAUUUCUUCCCUCAUUUUGCUCCAACUCUUUCUUCUUCCUUACAAAAGAGACUUUUGCUUUUUUCGAAACAUUUCCCCAUGUUUUUCUGGGGUCUCGCUAUGUUGCCCAGGCUGGUCUCAAACUCCUGGGCUCAAGUGACCCUCCCAAGUAGCUCUUACUACAGGCGUGCACCAUUGCACCCAGCCCCAUUUAUUCAUGUCUUAUUUCACUUGAUCCUUAUCCCAUCCCAGGAAGGCAACAAGGGUGAGAACCCUGUGCUCAGGGAGGUUAGGUCUCUUGUCCAAGGGAAAACGAUUAUCCAGAGAAGAGACCUGGCCAGAACCUGGGUCCCCUGAGUCCUAGCCAUGCUUCCCAUGUGCCUUACUUGCUGAAGCACCCCCGGACUGCAGUGUGAACGUGCUGUGCAAUAGUGACACGCUGGGCUUCCCCACAAGGCUCCACCCUGAGGUCUUUUAAGCUGUCCUUAUGCCAGCCUAUUUCUUGUUUUUUGGGCCUUUUUUUUUGGAGAUAGGGUCUCACUCUGUCGCCCAGGCUGGAGUGCAAUGACGCAAUCUUGGCUUAUUGCAGUCUCGACCUCCUGGGCUCAAGAGAUCCUUCCACCUCAGCCACCUGAGUAGCUUGGACUACAGGUGUGCACCACCUCUCCCAGUUAAUUUUUGUAUUUUUAGUAGAGACAGAGUUAUGCCAUGUUACUCAGGCUGGUCUUGAACUCCUGGACUCAAGCGAUCAGCCUGCCUUAGCCUCCCAAAGUGCAGGGGUUACAGGCUUGAGCCAUUGCGCCUGACCUAUUUCUGGUUCUUAGGGCCCUGGAUGUUAGGAUGGAUUUCUGAAUUAAUAAUAAUAAUAAAACCCUCAUCAAGA